AUACUGUCUUACCCACAGGGCAAGAGCAACUGGGUGCCCAGGCUCGGGACACAAGACUGCAGAGCCAGGUGCCACACAGGUGUGGGGCCCGUGGACCAAGGAAGACCCUGGCCAGUUGGAGGAGAACUGCCAGGUAGCAAAGCCCAGACUUCUCUGGGGUCCUGCGCUCUGGGCUGCAAUGAGCUCUGCCUCCAGUGAGCCUGGCAAUGGGGACGCCUCCCAACAGCCCCUACUGGGGCUGGACACCGUGAUCCAGAGACUGGAGGACACCAUCCUGAGUCCCACAGCCAGCAGGGAAGACCGGGCGCUGACCGUGCGUGGGGAAGGCCGGCAGGCCUCGCCCACCCCCGUGCCCACCCGCAUCCGUGAGAUCGUGGCCGGCAGCCUGAGUGAGGAGCCACCCCAAGCAGGGGUACAGGAGCCGACAGCCACUGUGGCCCGAGUGCAAGAGGAGAACGAGCUCCUGCAGGAGGAGCUGACCCGGCUGGGGGACCUGCUGGCCCAGGCCAGCGCCGAGCGAGAUGAGCUGGCCAGCAGGUGCCGUGUGGUCAGCGAGCAGCUGCAGGCCCGGCUGGAGACCACCGAGGCUCAGCUGCGGAGGUCAGAGCUGGAGCACAGCGUGGAUCUGGAGGAGGCCCUUGGCCGUCUGGAGGCUGCCGAGGAGAGGAGCACCGGCCUCUGUCAGGUGAACGCGCUCCUGCGGGAGCAGCUGGAACAUAUGAAGAAGGCCAAUGACGCGCUGGGCCGGGAGCUGGCCGGGAUGACGGGCAGCGUGCAGCGCCUGCAGGGCGAGCUGGAGCUGAGGCGCUGGGCCCAGAGACAGACCCGGUCAGGGGGCCUGGGGCAGCCCCGGGACCUCCUCCUCCUGUGGAGACAGGCCGUGGUGCUGGGGACAGACCUGGCCGAGCUGCGUGUAGCCACUGAGAGGGGCCUCGCUGACCUGCAGGCAGACACGGCCAGGACAGCCCGCCGCCUGCACACCGCCUGCCUGAACCUCGACUCCAACCUGCGGCUGUCGGCCAGCAGCACGGCCAGCACCCUGGGGCAGCAGCUUCGGGACAAGGCUGGGGAGAUGCUGCAGCUGCAGGGCCGCUGGGACGCAGAGAAGGUGGCGCUCCAGGCCAGACUCUCGGAGCAAACCCUGCUGGUGGAGAAGCUUACAGAGCAGAAUGAGCAGAAGGCGAAGACCAUCGCUGCCCUCAGAACCGACCUGCAGAACCUGGUGGCCCAGGAGGACGCCCGGUGCCUGGAGCUGGCAGGUAGCAGCAUCACUGAAUUGGGGGAGCCACGGCGCCCACUGAGGAGCCCCCAACGUGCCACAUCCCCCCAUCAAGGGGCGUCCCCACCACACAUCUGCUCCCCAGCCACCCUGGACCCCGCACUGCAGGCCAUGCGGGCAGCCAUAGAGAGGCGGUGGCGGCGGGAACAGGAGCUGUGCCUGCAGCUGAAGUCCUCCCAGGCACUGGUGGCCAGUCUCCAGGAGCAGCUGUCCGAAAGCCGGCGGGAGCUGUGGGCCGCACAGAAGCUCCAGCAGGAGCGGGCUCGGGAGCAGGCACGGGAACGAGAGGCUCUUCGGGGCCAGCUGGAGGCCCAGAGGCUCGAGGUGCAGCAGUGCCGGGCAUCCUGCAAGCUCCUGGGGAGGGAGAAGGCUGCUCUGGAGAUGGUGGUGGAGGAGCUGAAAGGGAAGGCAGAUGCUGCAGAUGCGGAGAAGCAGGGGCUGGAGGCCGAGGCUGCAGAGCUGCAGAGAAGCCUCCUGCUGCAGGCAGAGCGGAGGGAGGAGCUGGCUCUGCGGAGGGAGCGGAGCUGCAGGGCACUGGAGACCAGUCAAGGCCGCCUGCAGCAGCUGGAGGAGAAGGUCUCCGGGCUCAGAGAGGAGCUGGCAUCGGUCCGGGAGGCACUGAGCACAGCACAGCUGCAGCGGGAUGUCGUGGAGAGUGAGAGGGAGGGACUGCGCAGCGCCCUGGCGCGGGCCGAGUGCAGCAAUGCGGACCUGGAGCUUCUUGUGAGGCGGCUGAAGUCGGAGGGAGUGGAGCAAAGGGACUCCCUGGCCGCAAUGGCCGCCUUGAUGGAGGGGUUGGCUCAGGACAAAAGUGCCCUGAACCACCUGGCUCUCCAGCUGGAGCAGGAGCGGGACCAGCUGCGGGAACAGCGGAAGACUCUGGAGCAGGAACGGGCCCGGGCCGGGGAGCAGCUGGCACAGGCGGAGCAGCAGCUGGCGCUGGAGCGGGCAGAGCGCAGGGGCCUGCAGCAGGCCUGCGGACGCCUGGAGCAGCGGCAGGAGCAGCUGGAGGGGCAGGCAGCCCUGCUGGGGCGAGAGAAGGCCCAGCUCCAGGAGCAGGUGGGCCAGGUCACAUGCCAGAAACAGGCCCUGGAGGAGCAGCUGGCUCAGAGCCUGCAGGACCAGGAGGCCCAGAUGGGCACUCUGCAGCAAGCCCUGCAAGGAAAGGAUGCUCUGUCUGAGGAGCGGGCCCAGCUGCUGGCCAAGCAGGAGGCCUUGGAGAGGCAGGGCCGGCUCGCAGCUGAAGAGGCAGCUGAUCUCAGGGUGGAGAGGGACUCCCUGGAGAGCAGCCUCCUUGAGGCCCAACAGCUGGCCACAAAGCUGCAGGAGCAGCUGGAGGAGGAAGCCCGGAGCGCAGGACUCGCGCGGCAGGCCUUGCAAGUGGAAAUGGAGCAGCUACAAAGUGACUGGGAGGUCCAGGAAAUGAAGCUGCGGCAGGACACGGUGCGGCUCCAGCGACAGGUGGCACAGCAGGAGCGGGAGGCACAGCGGGCCCUGGAGAGCCAGGCGUUGGCCCACCGAGAGGCCCUGGCACAGCUCCAAAGGGAGAAGGAGACCCUGAGCCUGACCCUGGCAGAGGAGAAGGAGGUAGCCAGAUGCCAGCUGGAGCAGGAGAAGGAGCUGGUGACAAAAAGUGCAGCUGAGAGGGAGGCUCUGAAGGGGGAAAUUCAGAGCCUGAAGCAGGAGCGGGACGAGAGCCUUCUCCAACUGGAGCACAAGAUGCAACAGGCCCUGUCCCUGAAAGAAACAGAGCGGAGCCUUCUGAGUGAGGAGCUCUCCAGGGCCAGGAGGACGCUAGAGCGGGUACAGCAGGAGGCACAGAGCCAGCAGGAGCAAGCGCAGGCCACCAUCAGUGCCACGACUGAGGAGCUGAAGGCCCUCCAGGCCCAGUUUGAGGAUGCCAUCACAGCCCAUCAGAGGGAGACCACGGCCCUACGCGAGAGCCUCCAGGACCUAGCGGCUGAGCGGGGCGAUGUGGAGAGAGAGGCUGAGAGGCUGCGGGCACAGCUGACCGUGGCCCAGGAGGGACUGGCCGCACUGCGCCAGGAGCUGCAGGGCGUCGAGGAGAGCCGGGAGGGGCUGCACAGGGAGGCCCAGGAGGCCCGCCGGGCGCUGAGUGACGAGGCCCGCGAGAAGGACGUACUGUUGCUUUUCAACAGCGAGCUGCGGGCCACCAUCUGCAGGGCCGAACAGGAGAAGGCCAGUUUUAAGCGGUCCAAGGAGGAGAAGGAGCAGAAGCUGCUCAUCCUGGAGGAGGCCCAGGCGGCGUUGCAGCAGGAGGCCAGUGCACUGCGGGCCCACCUGUGGGAGCUGGAGCAGGCAGGGGGGGACGCCCGUCAGGAGCUCCGGGAACUCCACAGACAGGUGAGGACACUGAAGGCCGAGAACCAGAGGAGGAGUGGAGAGGCCCAUGAGCUGCAGGCGCAGUGCUCGCAGGAGGUGCUGGAGCUGCGGAGGCAGGCAGCCAAGGCAGAGGCCAAGCACGAGGGUGCCCGGAAGGAGGUCCUGGGAUUGCAGAGGAAGUUGGCAGAGGUGGAGGCCGCAGGGGAGGCCCAUGGACAGCGGCUCCAGGAGCACCUCCGUGAGAGCCGGGGGGCUGAGCAGACCCUCCGAGCAGAGCUGCACAGUGUCACCAGGAAGCUGCAGGAAGCCAGUGGUGUGGCUGAUGCUCUCCAGGCUCGCCUGGACCAGGCCUGUCACCGAAUCCACAGCCUGGAGCAGGAGCUGGCCCAGGCUGAGGGUGCAAGGCAGGAUGCGGAGGCCCAGCUGGGCCGGCUGUGCUCCACGCUCCGCCGUGGCCUGGGGCUCCAGAGACAGAGCCCGUGGGCCUCCCCGGAGCAGCCUGGUUCCCCCACCAAAGGCUCCGACAGCUCCCAGGCUCUCCCUGGGCAACAGGGUACCAGCCCCCCAGCCAGGCCCCACUCGCCCCUCCGAUGGCCCUCGCCCACACCCGGAGGCCGCAGCUCAGAGCUCAUGGAUGUGGCCACCGUGCAGGACAUCCUGCGGGACUUUGUGCAGAAGCUCCGGGAAGCCCAGCGGGAGCGGGAUGACUCCCGCAUCCAGAUGGCGACCCUGAGCAGCCGGCUGAGCGAGGCAGAGUGCAGGUGUGCCCGGGCCCAGAGCCGCGUGGGGCAGCUGCAGAAAGCCCUGGCUGAGGCGGAAGAAGGCCAGCGCCGGGUGGAGGGCGCGCUGAGCAGCGCCCGGGCAGCACGUGCCCUGCAGAAGGAGGCGCUCCGCAGGCUGGAGUUGGAGCACCUGGCGAGCGUGCGUGCGGCAGGCCAGGAGAAGCGGCGGCUGCAGGAGCAACUGGAAACGCUGCGCCAGGCUCUUGAAGAGAGCAGGAGGCACAGCCAAGGUCUGGCCAAGCAGGGGAAGCUGCUGGAAGAACAGCUCACCAACUUGGAGCACAGGUGCCAGAAGGCUGAGGUAUCGCUGGAGCCCCUGCGACAGAUGGAGCAAGAGACACUGAAGAGGGAGGAGGAUGUGGCGAGGCUGGGGGCUGAGAAGGAGCAGCUGGACCAGUCUCUGAACAGCCUGCACCAGGAGGUGGACGGAGCCCUGAGGCAAAAUCAGCAGCUGCAGGCCCAGAUGACAGAGAUGGAGCAGGCCCACACCCAGCGGCUCCAGGACCUGACAGCUCAGCACCAGCGGGACCUGGCCACAGAGGCAGAGCGUCUCCAUGGGGCCCGGCCGCAGGCCACGCAGGCCCUGGAGUCCCAAGAAUGGACCCACCAGCAGCAGGUAAAGGUGCUGGAAGAGCAGGUGGCCAGCCUGAAGGAGCAACUGGACCAGGAAGUGCAGUGGCGGCAACAGGCCCACCUCGGCCAGGCCUUCCAGACAGGACAGUGAGCCCUGCUGCAUACCACCCAGCAGCCUAGCUGCCUUCAGCCCUGACUGGCCAGGGGCAGGCGGCCCUGGGGAAGGUGCUGGAGGCCCUAGGCUGCUGGGGGAACCACUGUUGGGAAAACCAAUGCCUUGUGCUCUGCACAAGAGGGACAAAGCUCAAAUGGGGUGGGCACGAUGACAGCAGAAAGCACAGGGUGCAGGCAGCCACCGCCCGGGCCACCACUCACUCUUCAGGGUCCUCAGGCAGUGGCACACUCUGAGCCCGCUGACCGCAGAGCUCCUCCCACCCCUGGAGACUCAGCCUGCAGCUGGUGCUGGACCAUGCUGCGGGUCGCUCAUCUCUGACAGCCCCUUCCCCUCCGGCAGAGAGCAGGGGCUUGGGCAUCCUCCCAGCCUGCCCCCGCCUGGCACCCUCCCAGCCUGCCCCCGCCUGGCACUCCGUUUCUGCUUUGGAGGAGCUGCUCUGACCAGACCCCCGGGGCCAGGCCCUGUCAGGCUGGCUUCCCCGGCUUCAUUCCGUGCCCUCAGCUCUGUAAACACGGGAAAACACGUGGGAAACAUUUCCACCAACCGGAGCCAAAAACAUAAUGUCCUGCAAGGCCAGCCACCACAUCCCCACGCCCAGCGGCUGUGAGCCUCCGCAUCCAGGAACUGCGGCCGUCACGGUGGCAGGUGGCUGGAAGUGACUCAGAUUCAAGUCCCCGUGACUCACUGGCCGCCAGAAGAAGGGGAGUGUAACACUUAAAGCUGUUACAGAGCCUCCCAUGUUCCCGGCCUGGAAAUGCUGGGAACGGUCCUGUGGGACUCCGGCUGGGUUGCUAUGGAGACCCAGGCGGCCAUCUUGGGCCUGUGGCGUGGGCCACCUGUGUCCAUCUGCACCCCUCGUCUCCAUCACCGUUGCUCAGAGUGACUUGUUCUCCUCUCCAAAGGGCCGCAUGCUUUAUAGGUGGUCAUUUGUGAUAUCUGUGGGGCACCAGCCAGCCCAGUGAAUCCCUGCAUGUGCCACAGGGGCCUCCCGUCCCAGUCGCAAGGACUCUGGCCUAAGGGUGCAAGGCCAGAGGCUCCCGGCCCCCACCCCAUCACAGUUACUGUGAGCCUUGGCUGAAUGUGCAACAGUGUCUAUUUCAAGAUCACUCUGGGACUUAAAAUAGUCUGUCCUGGCACACCUGGUUUUCUGGUGGAUUUAGUAAUGGAGUUACCAUAUGCUGUAAAUCAUGCAAAAUCAAUAACUCAAGAGAGGUGGGCAUAUAGGCUCCUUCCUGUCUGUUACCUCUGCCUGAUUGUUGGUGGCUGUGUUGAGAAGGAUUCUGAGGCUCAGCCUGGGCUCUGAGGGGAAGAGCUUGGUGACCCAUGAGUGGAUGUUACUCUGGGCAAAGGAGGAGUCAGUGGUGGCACAGGUGCCCCGAUAGGCACCCCCUGCCAUGGCCAGUCAGGGGUGGAGGACAGCAGGCAGGCCUGCCCCCACUGCUGGAGAGUGCUCUGCCAGAUGGUGGGUGGAGGGGGUCACUGAGAGGCAGCGUGUGGUGCUCAGGGCCUGGCACUUAGUAGGCAUGUCCCUUCCCUGCCUUCCUUCCCCAUUCGCAGUCUCCUCAUAGAGGGGGCCUCCCGCUCUGCAGCCCAGCAGAAGGGCCUGAGGGAUGGCCAGGGCGGGAGGGAGGAACAGAAGUUCAAGGUUCCCAGUUGUGGGCAGGAGACUCAGCAUCGGUCCCUCCAGCCCCCGGCAGCAGGAGCCCCCAUGUGUCCCCGGGAAUGCGGUGUCCACGCCUCCCUCUUUGCAUCCCUGCAGCGCCCAAAGGGACUGAAGCUCCCAGCACAGGGGAGGCGCCCAGCGUGGCUGCAGAGGAAGGGAACGCACCGCAGGUGGGAGGGGCCCAGCUGAUUUCUCAGCGUCACAGUGAAAGGCACCCGUGAUGAGACAGCUCGCUCUCGGCAGUUUCAGGACCCUCCUUGCCCUGGCUGCUCAUGGGGAACAUUUGAAAUGCAUGUGGGGGCCUCCGAAUUUUGAAUUUUAAUAAAUAGUUGAAUCAGCGUA